GCAGUCGGGCCCUCUGCGCGCUGCGCCCGAAGCGGCGGUCGGUGGCAGGGGUGGUAGCGGCGGCGGCGACGGUUUCGUGGGGGCCGCGCGCUGCUCUGUGAGCGGCGGGUGGCAGCAGGGGACUCCUGACACUUCCCCUUCCCCACCGAACCGCGCUUUCUGAAACAAAGACUCAUUUUGAAGAUGUUUAACAAAUCAUUUGGAACACCCUUUGGGGGUGGCACAGGUGGCUUUGGCACAACUUCAACAUUUGGACAGAAUACUGGCUUUGGCACUACUAGUGGAGGGGCAUUUGGAACAUCUGCAUUUGGUUCUAGCAACAAUACUGGAGGCCUCUUUGGAAAUUCACAGACUAAACCAGGAGGAUUGUUUGGAACCAGUUCAUUUAGCCAGCCAGCUACCUCCACAAGCACUGGCUUUGGGUUUGGUACGUCAACAGGAACAGCAAAUACCUUGUUUGGAACUGCAAGCACAGGGACCAGUCUCUUCUCAUCCCAAAACAAUGCCUUUGCACAAAAUAAACCAACUGGCUUUGGCAAUUUUGGAACCAGUACUAGCAGUGGAGGACUCUUUGGAACCACAAAUACCACCUCUAAUCCUUUUGGCAGCACAUCUGGCUCCCUCUUUGGGCCAAGUAGUUUUACAGCUGCUCCUACUGGGACUACUAUUAAAUUUAACCCUCCAACUGGUACAGAUACUAUGGUCAAAGCUGGAGUUAGCACUAACAUAAGUACCAAGCACCAGUGUAUUACUGCUAUGAAAGAAUAUGAAAGCAAGUCACUAGAGGAACUUCGUUUAGAGGAUUAUCAGGCUAACAGGAAGGGCCCACAGAACCAGGUGGGAGCAGGUACCACAACUGGCUUGUUUGGGUCUUCUCCAGCCACUUCCAGCGCAACAGGACUCUUCAGCUCCUCCACCACUAAUUCAGGCUUUGCAUAUGGUCAGAACAAAACUGCCUUUGGAACUAGUACAACUGGAUUUGGAACAAAUCCAGGUGGUCUCUUUGGCCAACAGAAUCAGCAGACUACCAGCCUCUUCAGCAAACCAUUUGGCCAGGCUACAACCACCCAGAACACUGGCUUUUCCUUUGGUAAUACCAGCACCAUAGGACAGCCAAGCACCAACACCAUGGGAUUAUUUGGAGUAACCCAAGCCUCACAGCCUGGAGGUCUUUUUGGGACAGCUACAAACACCAGCACUGGGACAGCAUUUGGAACAGGAACAGGUCUCUUUGGGCAGACCAAUACUGGAUUUGGUGCUGUUGGUUCGACCCUGUUUGGCAAUAACAAGCUUACUACAUUUGGAAGCAGCACAACCAGUGCACCUUCAUUUGGUACAACCAGUGGCGGGCUCUUUGGUUUUGGCACAAAUACCAGUGGGAAUAGUAUUUUUGGAAGUAAACCAGCACCUGGGACUCUUGGAACUGGGCUUGGUGCAGGAUUUGGAACAGCUCUUGGUGCUGGACAGGCAUCUUUGUUUGGGAACAACCAACCUAAGAUUGGAGGGCCUCUUGGUACAGGAGCCUUUGGGGCCCCUGGAUUUAAUACUACGACAGCCACUUUGGGCUUUGGAGCCCCCCAGGCCCCAGUAGCUUUGACAGAUCCAAAUGCUUCUGCUGCCCAGCAGGCUGUUCUCCAGCAGCACAUCAAUAGUCUAACAUACUCACCUUUUGGAGACUCUCCUCUCUUCCGGAAUCCGAUGUCAGACCCUAAGAAGAAGGAAGAGAGAUUGAAACCAACAAAUCCAGCAGCCCAGAAGGCUCUUACUACACCUACUCAUUAUAAACUGACACCCCGCCCUGCCACUAGAGUCCGGCCAAAGGCUUUACAAACAACAGGCACAGCCAAGUCACAUCUCUUUGAUGGGCUGGAUGACGAUGAACCAUCCCUAGCCAAUGGAGCAUUCAUGCCCAAGAAGAGCAUUAAGAAGUUGGUUUUGAAGAACCUUAAUAAUAGCAAUCUCUUUUCUCCUGUUAAUCGUGAUUCAGAAAAUCUAGCUUCACCAUCUGAAUAUCCAGAAAAUGGAGAGAGAUUUAGUUUCCUAAGCAAACCUGUUGAUGAGAAUCACCAGCAGGAUGGAGAUGAAGAUUCCCUUGUUUCACAUUUUUAUACUAACCCUAUUGCCAAACCUAUUCCUCAAACCCCAGAAAGUGCUGGAAAUAAACACAGCAACAGCAACAGUGUGGAUGAUACCAUUGUUGCAUUAAACAUGCGUGCUGCUUUGCGAAAUGGGCUGGAAGGAAGCAGUGAAGAAACGUCUUUUCAUGAUGAGUCACUUCAGGAUGACCGAGAAGAAAUAGAAAAUAAUUCUUACCAUAUGCACCCAGCAGGUAUUAUUCUCACUAAGGUUGGUUACUAUACUAUUCCAUCUAUGGAUGACCUUGCUAAAAUUACCAAUGAAAAAGGAGAGUGCAUUGUCUCUGAUUUCACUAUUGGUCGGAAAGGUUAUGGUUCAAUCUAUUUUGAAGGAGAUGUGAAUUUGACAAAUCUAAAUUUGGAUGAUAUUGUGCAUAUCCGGAGGAAAGAAGUAGUUGUCUACUUAGAUGAUAACCAAAAACCACCUGUGGGUGAAGGGCUAAAUAGGAAGGCUGAAGUUACAUUGGAUGGAGUUUGGCCAACAGAUAAAACAUCUCGUUGUUUAAUAAAGAGCCCAGAUCGCCUUGCUGAUAUCAACUAUGAAGGAAGAUUGGAAGCAGUUUCAAGGAAACAGGGAGCUCAAUUCAAAGAAUACCGGCCUGAAACUGGUUCUUGGGUGUUUAAGGUCUCCCAUUUUUCUAAGUAUGGCCUUCAGGAUUCUGAUGAAGAGGAGGAGGAGCAUCCGUCUAAAACUAGUACAAAGAAGUUGAAGACUGCUCCUUUGCCUCCUGCAAGCCAGACUACGCCCUUGCAGAUGGCUCUUAAUGGCAAACCUGCACCUCCACCUCAGAGCCAGAGCCCAGAGGUGGAGCAGUUAGGGAGGGUUGUGGAACUGGACAGUGACAUGGUAGAUAUCACCCAGGAGCCAGUUUUGGAUACCAUGUUAGAAGAGAGCAUGCCUGAGGAUCAGGAACCUGUGUCUGCCUCAACACAUAUUGCAUCUUCACUGGGAAUUAAUCCACAUGUCUUACAGAUCAUGAAAGCAUCAUUGCUUACUGAUGAAGAAGAUGUAGAUAUGGCACUGGAUCAACGCUUCAGUCGCCUGCCUUCCAAAGCAGAUACUUCUCAAGAAAUCUGUUCUCCCAGACUCCCCAUUUCAGCAUCCCACUCGUCGAAAACUCGUUCACUAGAGAUGGAUCUUGCUAUCUUGCCCCAGGCUGGUCUUGAACUUCUGGCCUCAACUGAUCAUCCUGCCUCAGCUUCCCAAAGUGCUGAGAUUACAGUUGGUGGGUUACUACAAUCAAAAUUUACAAGUGGAGCUUUUCUUUCACCAAGUGUCUCUGUGCAAGAAUGUCGUACUCCCAGAGCAGCAUCUUUAAUGAAUAUCCCAUCCACAUCCUCUUGGUCUGUCCCUCCACCCCUGACUUCUGUGUUCACAAUGCCCAGCCCAGCCCCUGAGGUUCCGUUGAAAACAGUGGGUACACGUAGGCAACUAGGCCUAGUCCCUCGUGAAAAGUCUGUCACCUAUGGCAAGGGAAAACUCUUGAUGGACAUGGCCCUAUUCAUGGGACGCUCAUUUCGUGUUGGUUGGGGCCCCAACUGGACUCUUGCUAAUAGUGGAGAACAGCUGAAUGGCUCUCAUGAACUAGAAAAUCAUCAGAUUGCCGAUUCCAUGGAGUUUGGAUUCCUGCCCAAUCCAGUAGCUGUUAAACCCCUAACUGAGUCCCCAUUCAAAGUUCACUUAGAAAAACUCAGUUUGAGACAAAGAAAGCCAGAUGAAGACAUGAAAUUAUAUCAGACACCUCUGGAGCUCAAAUUAAAACACAGCACUGUCCAUGUGGAUGAACUGUGUCCUCUCAUUGUCCCCAAUCUGGGAGUUGCUGUCAUUCAUGACUAUGCAGAUUGGGUUAAAGAAGCAUCAGGAGACUUACCAGAAGCACAAAUUGUGAAGCACUGGAGCCUGACAUGGACACUAUGUGAAGCCCUAUGGGGCCACCUGAAGGAGCUUGACAGCCAGCUAAAUGAACCCCGUGAAUACAUUCAAAUUCUGGAGCGAAGAAGAGCUUUCUCCCGCUGGCUAUCCUGUACUGCCACACCUCAGAUUGAAGAGGAAGUCUCCUUAACCCAAAAAAACAGCCCUGUGGAGGCUGUAUUCAGCUACCUCACAGGCAAAAGGAUCAGUGAGGCCUGCUCUCUGGCCCAGCAGUCAGGGGAUCAUCGUCUUGCUCUUCUUUUAUCUCAGUUUGUGGGUAGCCAGUCAGUCCGGGAGCUGCUCACCAUGCAGUUGGUGGACUGGCAUCAGCUCCAAGCAGACUCCUUCAUCCAGGAUGAGAGACUGCGCAUCUUUGCUCUGUUGGCUGGAAAACCGGUGUGGCAGCUCUCAGAAAAGAAGCAAAUAAACGUGUGCUCCCAGUUGGAUUGGAAACGCUCCCUGGCUAUCCAUCUUUGGUAUUUGCUUCCACCAACAGCCUCCAUUUCUAGGGCGCUCAGCAUGUAUGAAGAAGCAUUUCAGAAUACCUCUGACAGUGACAGAUAUGCCUGCUCCCCACUUCCUUCGUAUCUGGAGGGUUCUGGCUGUGUGAUAGCGGAGGAGCAAAACUCACAGACACCACUUCGAGAUGUCUGCUUUCACCUUCUAAAACUCUACAGUGACAGACAUUAUGAUCUCAACCAGCUGCUGGAGCCUCGAAGCAUAACAGCAGAUCCUUUGGACUACCGCCUAAGCUGGCACUUGUGGGAAGUGCUGAGGGCUCUUAACUACACCCAUCUCUCAGCGCAGUGUGAAGGUGUGCUACAGGCCAGUUACGCUGGCCAGCUUGAAAGUGAGGGGCUCUGGGAGUGGGCCAUCUUUGUCCUCCUGCACAUUGACAACUCAGGCAUACGUGAGAAGGCUGUUCGAGAGCUGCUUACCCGGCACUGCCAGCUGUUGGAGACCCCUGAAUCUUGGGCUAAAGAGACUUUCCUUACCCAGAAGCUCCGUGUACCUGCCAAAUGGAUCCACGAGGCCAAAGCUGUGCGAGCACACAUGGAAUCUGACAAGCACUUAGAGGCCCUUUGCUUAUUUAAGGCUGAGCACUGGAACCGCUGCCACAAGCUCAUCAUCCGACACUUAGCUUCUGAUGCCAUCAUUAAUGAGAACUAUGACUACCUGAAGGGGUUCUUGGAAGACCUGGCACCUCCAGAGCGCAGCAGCCUAAUUCAGGAUUGGGAAACAUCUGGGCUUGUUUACCUGGACUAUAUUAGAGUCAUUGAAAUGCUCCGCCAUAUACAGCAGGUGGAUUGCUCAGGUAAUGACCUGGAGCAGUUACACAUCAAAGUGACUUCACUGUGCAGUCGGAUAGAGCAGAUUCAGUGUUACAGUGCUAAAGAUCGCCUGGCUCAGUCAGACAUGGCCAAACGUGUAGCCAACCUGCUGCGCGUGGUGCUGAGUCUGCAUCAUCCUCCUGAUAGAACCUCCGACUCAACACCAGACCCUCAGCGAGUCCCUUUGCGCCUCUUGGCUCCCCACAUUGGCCGGCUUCCCAUGCCUGAGGACUAUGCCAUGGACGAACUGCGCAGCCUUACCCAGUCCUAUCUGCGAGAACUGGCUGUUGGGAGCCUGUGAGCCCCAGGCACUUUGCAUCACAGUCACAUGCCCAUUCACACCACACAGAGGUUCCCUGCCUUGUUUGGAUUGGCACUGUUUGCCAUUCUCUGGGUUGGCUGUGGCAUCUACCCUCCCUCCCUGCUGCCAGAAGCAGCAUCCUCCACUUGUUCAGGGCUUUUCUUAAUACUGAACGUAGCAUAAGGGCUUCUGGAACCCAGAAGAGGAGACAGUUUACCAUCCUCAAGAUCAUUCAGUGUUUUUCCUUUAAAAAAAUGGUCAAUAAAGCUCCUUUGGCAGAAUCCCCCAAAGAACCAGGGUAUUCUUUUUCCAUCCCUAGCCAUUCUGGAUCUUGUGACCCUCCAUGCCAACCAGCUUCCCUACUCCUACCCUGGCCCUUUUAUACUAGGACUCCUUAGGAGGAGUGAGACAGGUGAUAAUGGAUCCUUAACAGAUGAACUAUCCACAGAAGGAAGAGGGAUCCGUCUCUUAAGUAAUUGGUUAGUUAACACUGAAUUUUGGAGGCAAAGGAGGGUUGGCCUGAGUUAGGAAACAAAAUGGGAUCUUUCUGACACACUUAGGGCAGAAGUGAAUGCCUGUCACGGAGGGAUUGAUCUUCAGGGCUGUUUUUGUUCCUGCCUUUAGAGUUCCAUGAACACCAUACCUUUGCUACUACUAUGUGCAGGAACCCUUGGUCACAUGUGACAUGUCUGUGGGAAGCUCCCAGAGUUUGGUUUGGUCCCUGGUUUUCAGUCUUGCUGAGACUCUGUCUGGAUUUGCCUGCAGAGUUUGGAUAAAAAAUGGCAGGUUGGGUAACCCUCCCUGUUCAUCCCAUGUUAGCUCCAAAGCAUUUCCCACCCUCCAUCUACCCCUUCCAGAAGCAAAAACAAACCAUGACUGAGGCAGGCAUGGAGUUGGGCGUUAGGGGCAGGCAGAGGGCCUUUGCUACACUGCUGACAGCUAUAGGGAGCCCCAGGUAAUGGCAUGAGAUAGCUGGUGUUAGGGCUAUCUCAGGCAAUAUGGCCACACCUGGGUCUUUAUGCAUGAAGAUAAUGUAAAGGUUUUUAUUAAAAAAUAUAUAUAUGUAUAAAUAAAUGAUCUAGAUAUUUUCCUCUUUUUCUGAAGCUACUUUCUUAAAAAAUAAAUAAAAUGUUUAUAGCA